GCUUUAGCUUAGCAGGCGACGUUGCGGGCCCUGGGCGCCAGGAGAGCUUCCCGGAGUCGACCUUCCUGCUGGCUGCUCUGUGACCGCUUCCCGGCUCUGCCCUCUUGGCCGAAGUGCCCGCUGCCGGGCGCGGGCCUCAGGUAACGGUGGUGCUCCCGCGCCUCUCCUCGCUUCCCGCUUGGGUCCACCGGCCUCAGCCCGCGGGGAAGGGAGAAGCGGUGGCGGCAGCAGCUCCGGCCCGGCCUUGUCCUGGGCUGUGCUGCGGAGAAGGCGAGGCUCGGCGACUGCAGGGGAGUUGGGGAGGGGAGGGCGGGAAAGUUACCGUCAGGCGCCCGGGUCACGGGCAGCCUUUUAAACCCUGCACGCUGGUUUGGUGUUCCGCAAAUCUCGUGGCAUCUCUCAAGUCAGUAGUAAAGAAAGUUAGGAAUUAGAAGACGUUUUAUUCUUUAAAAAGCGAAACCAAAAAUGCACUCAGGAAGUCAGCUUUUUAAUGAUUUAGAGAAAAUGUGUGAAGGGAAGGAUGGUAUUAGCAAGACAUGAAAAUCUGUAGGGGCACCAGAACCUUUAAUCAAGCUCAUGUUUUAUUGUAAAAUAUUAGGAUGUAGACAAUACAAUGGUGGGUGAAGAGAAGAUGUCUCUAAGAAACCGGCUGUCAAAGUCCAGGGAAAAUCCUGAGGAAGAUGAAGACCAGAGAAACCCUGCAAAGGAGUCCCUAGAGACACCUAGUAAUGGUCGAAUUGACAUAAAACAGUUGAUAGCAAAGAAGAUAAAGUUGACAGCAGAGGCAGAGGAAUUGAAGCCAUUUUUUAUGAAGGAAGUUGGCAGUCACUUUGAUGAUUUUGUGACCAAUCUCAUUGAAAAGUCAGCAUCAUUAGAUAAUGGUGGGUGCGCUCUCACAACCUUUUCUGUUCUUGAAGGAGAGAAAAACAACCAUAGAGCGAAGGAUUUGAGAGCACCUCCAGAACAAGGAAAGAUUUUUAUUGCAAGGCGCUCUCUCUUAGAUGAACUGCUUGAAGUGGACCACAUCAGAACAAUAUAUCACAUGUUUAUUGCCCUCCUCAUUCUCUUUAUCCUCAGCACACUUGUAGUAGAUUACAUUGAUGAAGGAAGGCUGGUGCUUGAGUUCAGCCUCCUGUCUUAUGCUUUUGGCAAAUUUCCUACCGUUGUUUGGACCUGGUGGAUCAUGUUCCUGUCUACAUUUUCAGUUCCCUAUUUUCUGUUUCAACAUUGGGCCACUGGCUAUAGCAAGAGUUCUCAUCCGCUGAUCCGUUCUCUCUUCCAUGGCUUUCUUUUCAUGAUCUUCCAGAUUGGAGUUCUAGGUUUUGGACCAACAUAUGUUGUGUUAGCAUAUACACUGCCACCAGCUUCCCGGUUCAUCAUUAUAUUCGAGCAGAUUCGUUUUGUAAUGAAGGCCCACUCAUUUGUCAGAGAGAACGUGCCUCGGGUACUAAAUUCAGCUAAGGAGAAAUCAAGCACUGUUCCAAUACCUACAGUCAACCAGUAUUUGUACUUCUUAUUUGCUCCUACCCUUAUCUACCGUGACAGCUAUCCCAGGAAUCCCACUGUAAGAUGGGGUUAUGUCGCUAUGAAGUUUGCACAGGUCUUUGGUUGCUUUUUCUAUGUGUACUACAUCUUUGAAAGGCUUUGUGCCCCCUUGUUUCGGAAUAUCAAACAGGAGCCCUUCAGCGCUCGUGUUCUGGUCCUAUGUGUAUUUAACUCCAUCUUGCCAGGUGUGCUGAUUCUCUUCCUUACUUUUUUUGCCUUUUUGCACUGCUGGCUCAAUGCCUUUGCUGAGAUGUUACGCUUUGGUGACAGGAUGUUCUAUAAGGAUUGGUGGAACUCCACGUCAUACUCCAACUAUUAUAGAACCUGGAAUGUGGUGGUCCAUGACUGGCUAUAUUACUAUGCUUACAAGGACUUUCUCUGGUUUUUCUCCAAGAGAUUCAAAUCUGCUGCCAUGUUAGCUGUCUUUGCUGUAUCUGCUGUAGUACACGAAUAUGCCUUGGCUGUUUGCUUGAGCUUUUUCUAUCCCGUGCUCUUCGUGCUCUUCAUGUUCUUUGGAAUGGCUUUCAACUUCAUUGUCAAUGAUAGUCGGAAAAAGCCGAUUUGGAAUGUUCUGAUGUGGACUUCUCUUUUCUUGGGCAAUGGAGUCUUACUCUGCUUUUAUUCUCAAGAAUGGUAUGCACGUCAGCACUGUCCUCUGAAAAAUCCCACAUUUUUGGAUUAUGUCCGGCCACGUUCCUGGACUUGUCGUUACGUGUUUUAGAAGCUUGGACUUUGUUUCCUCCUUGUCACUGAAGAUUGGGUAGCUCCCUGAUUUGGAGCCAGCUGUUUCCAGUUGUUACUGAAGUUAUCUGUGUUAUUUGGACCACUCCAGGCUUUACAGAUGACUCACUCCAUUCCUAGGUCACUUGAAGCCAAACUGUUGGAAGUUCACUGGAGUCUUGUACACUUAAGCAGAGCAGAACUUUUUUUGUGGGGCUGGGUGGGGGGAGAAGACCGACUAACAGCUGAAGUAAUGACAGAUUGUUGCUGGGUCAUAUCAGCUUUAUCCCUUGGUAAUUAUAUCUGUUUUGUUUCUUGACUCUGUCCAAUCAGAGAAUAAACAUCAUAGUUUCUUGGCCACUGAAUUAGCCAAAACACUUAGGAAGAAAUCACUUAAAUACCUCUGGCUUAGAAAUUUUUUCAUGCACACUGUUGGAAUGUAUGCUAAUUGAACAUGCAAUUGGGGAAGAAAAAAUGUAGAAUGAUUUUUGCUAUUUCUAGUAGAAAGAAAAUGUCUGUUUUCCAAAGAUAAUGUUAUACAUCCUAUUUUGUAAUUUUUUUGAAAAAAGUUCAAUGUUCAGUUUUCCUUAGUUUUUACCUUGUUUUCUCUAUAGGUCAUGAUUUCUGUGAAGCAAAAAGAUGCCUUUUACCAUGAAUUCUUGAGUUUACAUCAAUAAUAUUGUAUAUUAAGGGGAUCAGAAGUAGGAAGGAAAAAAUAAGAGAUAGCAGAGGAAAAAGAAAAACAUUUCCUCUUAUAACUUCUGAAGUAAUUUGUAAAAAAGAUUUGUAGAGUCAAUCAUGUGUUUAAAUUAUUUUAUCACAAACUUAACAUGGAAGAUAUUCCUUUUUAACUUUGUGGUAACUUCUUUGAAGUUAUUUAGAAAUAUCCUUUGGAACAAUUAUUUUAUUGUCUAAUAAAUAUUGACUUCUCUUGAAUUAUUUUGCAGACUAGUGAGUCUGUACCAUAAGUAUUAAUCACCUCCACUCAUAUUAAAGUGAUCAUUAAGAAUCCAGAAGCUGGCUUCUGCAUUUGCUCAGUUAUACUUUUAAUGGUAGUAUGUUUUUAGGUGGAAUAAAUUAAUAUGUGAUUGGUUUCAAGGAAAUGUACUCUAUUAUGUAAUACUUCCAUUUUAUAAGAUGCCCAUUUCUAAUACAAUGUGUGUAGGAAUUAUUUGUAUGUAUGAGGUAUGAUUGUAAAGAUUGAGCAUUGGAAGGGGUAUCAGAGACCAUGUAGUUCAACUUUCCACUCAAAGUAAGAUUUAUGAAUUAUUUAAAUGAUAGUUGUUACUUGGAACAGCCACUUGAGAGGCUCUCUUGGUAUUGUUUGGAAUUGUUUUAAAGUCAGUUUGAGUCUCACAAGAAGGUAAGUAGAGUUUCUUAAUAGUCACAACUUAAUUUGAACCACAAGUAUCCAGCUUAAUCACGUAUCUUACUCACGAUACCACUGGUCCAGAUGAGUUUAGGUAAUUUUCAAACAUUAAAUCCAACUUCAACGGAAACAAAUACACUCAAGGGAAGUUAUUUUUAAAAAGGUACUCUGCAUGUUCCCGCAGUAAUGUUCUGCACAACAGUAUUGUAAUUGUAAUGGAAUCAUAACCUGCUAACUAGUUUGCUUUAAUAUGGCUUGUAAUUCUUGACAUUUUUCUUAAAAUUAAAACGAAUUUUUAUUUUGAAUUUAUAACUGCAUUUUAAAUAUAUUGGGGACAGAUUGCGCUGAGACCUGGUUAUGAGCAAGCCAAUCUUUUGAAUCUAGAGAAUGGAAUUCUUAGGUUUAUAUUUCUGUUAAGAAAUACUAUAAAUAUGACUCUUAUGAGAAGACUUUGUUGCUCUGUAGUGUUUCUGAAUACUGUAUUUGUUGGAUUGAUCAAGGCUAUUUUUCAAAAAGCUCUCUGCUUCCUGUUUGUUUGUUUGUUUGUUUUUGAGACAGAGUCUUGCUCUGUCGCCGGGGCUGGAGUGCAAUGGCGUGAACUCAGCUCACUGCAACCUCUGCCUCCCUGGUUCAAGCUAUUCUCCUGCCUCAGCCUCCUGAGUAGCUGGGAUUACAGGGCCACGCCUGGCUAAUUUUUGUAUUUUUAGUAGAGAUGGGGUUUCACCCUGUUGGUCAGGCUGGUCUCAAACUCCUGACCUUGUGAUCUGCCCACCUCAGCCUCCCAAAGUGCUGGGAAGACAGGCGUUAGCCACCGUGCCCGGCCUCUGUUUCCUGUUAUUAGUGAUUUUCCUGCCCAAGAUUGCAACAACAAAUAUGUAGAACUACAGACUGUUUAGAAUGCUGAGACUGUUCUAAGAAACUUUCAAAAACAGUAGCACUUCAAGGAAUGGUCACUUUCUAUGAAAGAAACUGGUUUGAUAGCCAUAAUCUUAUUGCUAGCUGCUUUUAGCAAAAGUCUUUUCUUGAAACCACCACCUAUACUCUUUAAACAAAUAAAAACUAAAAUCUCUUGCUAAUGUUUCAGGAAGAUUUAUUUUUUCUAUUUUGCUAUUGUGGCGAAAAUUAUUUUCAGUUAUAGGAUACUUUUUUCCUUCUGAAAAGUAAUAAGCUUAAAGUUUUUGUUUCUGUAAGAUGUAAUGAUAGUAACUAUUAUUUUGGGCAUAUUAACCAACAGAACAAUUAUGUAGUAUGUAUAUCACUUUCUCAUUAGAUCUCUAACUUGACCUUCUAGUACCUUUAUGUGUGAGGAUAAAUUUGUUAGAUCCUUUUAUUCUCAAUCUUGGAUAAUGAUGCAAAAUGGAAUUUUGUUUUGUUUGUUGGUAGAUUCACAUACUAAAACUUUGCAGGUAAAGUUGCUUGCCUCAUGUUAGAAUUUAAUUAGAAAACUGAGGCUGCCUUUUUUUUUUUUUUUUUUUUUUUUUAAGACAGAGUCUUGUUCUGUCGCCCAGGCCAGUUUUUUUUUUCUUGUACAGAUGGGGUUUUACCAUGUUGCUCAGGCUGGUCUCAAACUCCUGGAGUCAAGGGAUCUAUUUGCCUCAGCCUCUCAAAGUGCUGGGAUUACAGGUGUGAGCCACGGCUCCUGGCUCCUUGCUCCAGAAUCAGUUUUUUAAUGGAAGAUAGCUCAUACUUUGUUUUUGUUUUUAAAGAGACAGGGUCUCACUCUGUUGCCCAGGCUGGUAGUAGCGUGAUCAUAGCUCACUGCAGUCUCAAACUCCUGGACUCAAAUAGUGCUCUGGAGUACCUAGAACUACAAGUGCCUACCACCACACCCAGCUAAUUUAUUUGUUUUUUUUUUUUUAGAGAUGGGGGGGGUCUCCCUAUGUUGCCCAGGCUGGUCUCAAACUCUUCACCUCAAGCAAAACUCCCACUGCAGAAAGCUUUGGGAUUACAGGCAUGAGCCACCAUGCCAAGCCCAUACUUAUUGUUAAUAAAGUUUCAGUGACUUGCUUACUAAUCUUAUGCAAAAUUUCAUGUAAUUUAUGUAAUACUACAUAACAAUGCUACAUAUGGUAUGUAUACAUACACUGUAUACACACAAAGGUCUGUUCUGGGUAUUUUAUGUAUCUUAUCUCUAGGCUUUAUGGCUCUGAAAUGGAGGGAACUGGACAUAAAUGUUUCAAGGAAUAAAGUGAAUGUUUUGUUUGUUUGUUUGUUUUGAGACGGAGUCUCAGUCACCAGGCUGGAGUGCAGUGCUGUGAUCUCAGCUCACUGCAACCUCUGCCUCCUGGGUUCAAGCGAUUCUCCUGCCUCAGCCUCCCGAGUAGCUGGCAUUACAGGUGCCUGCCACCAUGUCCAGCUAAUUUUUGUGUUUUUAGUAGAGAUGGGGUUUCACCAUGAUGGUCAGGCUGGUCUCGAACUCCUGACCUCAUGAUCCGCCAGCCUCAGCCUCCCAUAGUGCUGGGAUUAUAGGCAUGAGCCAUGCUCCCGGCCAAAGUGAAUGUUUUGGGUGAAGUUUAUAUAAGGAUUUGACUUUUGUAUCAUUAUUAAAGUUUCUGUCAGGUAAUACAGUGUUGGCCCUCUGUUGAAAUAAAAUGUUACAUAUCGCUGGGUGUAGUGGCUCAUGCCUUUAAUCCCAGUACUUUGGGAGGCCAAGGCAGGAGGAUUGCUUGAGCUCAGAAGUUUGAGACCAGCCUGGGCAACAUAGCAAAACCUUGUCACUAUAAAAAAUACAAAAAUUAGCCAGGCGUGGUGGUGCACGCCUGUAGUCUCAGCUACUCAGUCGGCUGAGGUGGGAAGAUGGCUUCAAGCCGGGAGAUGGAGGCUUCAGUGACCUGUGACCUGUGAUCACACCACUUAAUUCCUCAAAACAUUUAUGUCCCAGUUCCCUCCAUUUCAGAGCCAUGGGCAACAGAGCGAGACCCUGUCUCAAAAAAAAAAUUACAUAUAAGCCCGGUUUAAAGAGAGGAUAAUAUGCAACCACCCUAGUUGAAACAGAGUGUAUCACUUCUUUCUCACCCUAAAUUUAAUGCCUAGUUUGAAAAUCAGUAGACAAUAAUAAAGUUGAUAAGCUUUAGGUUGGUAGGAAAGCUAUGUAAUCUAUAUAGUGUACUAAAUCCUUAUAUGUUUUUGGUAAAAAAAGACUUUAAUAGCUAAUUUGGACUUCAGAAAAUGGGUUAAUUUCACGAGUGCAUAUCACUUUUGACUAUAUUAGUCAAGCAUAUUAUUAAAGUUUAAAAAACUCUAAAACUUCUGUACUGUUUUUUUCUUAAGUGCUCUCUUCCUUAUUUCUACAUUACUACAUUCACAUUUCUGCUGUCAAUAAGCCCUAAUGGAGUGAUAAACUUUAAGCUAGUAGAUACUGCACCAUGUCUUGUGGUGGUGUUUUCUUAAUGAAAUGGAAGCUGUACUUCCUGUUUGUUUUUAAAUACUUUUGAAACAGACAGUUCAUGUACCCCAUCAUUUAGAGAUGCAGUUUGAAUUUCCAUGGAAAAAGGUGCCAAUUUUGGAUUGGGAAAGGAGCUGAAGCCCCAGUCAAGACUUUGCCAUUUGGGGUAAUGCAGCAGAUUCCUGUGUCUGUAUCUUUCCAGUGUGUGUGUUAAUCCAUAGUGUUCUGAGCACCAGAAGGGUCAUGUAAAUCUGAAGUUGUUAUUAAAGGUUUUUCUAUAGUGAAA